AGUUCAGCCACCAGCUCUGCCAGCAGGGUCCCAGCAGCAGCAGCAUCAGAGGCAGGGACUGGGCUCCUGGGGGUAGGGCCCCGGCCCCUCUGGCACAGCUGGUCAGCAGCUUCCAUGGGGGGCCCUGUGUGGAGACACAGUGUCCAGCACCGAUUUCUGGGCCUGAUGCUGCCCCAGCUGAGUCCCGCAGCAAGCGCAAGAGAGAGAAGUGCUUGGUGUCCACCUCUGAGAAGGCCUCCUGUGUGAACACGGCCCCCUGAGGGGCCAGGCAAGGGCGUCUGCUCCUGUGGCUGGGACGGUUCCUGCCCACGAGCCUUGUGUAGGGCUGCGGCUCUCUUCCCAGAUGGAGAAUGAGGCACAGAGAAGUUAAGUAACUUGCCCAACGUCACACAGCUAAGAAUCUCGAUGCUGGCCUGGAGCAGAAACUGAGCUGGACCACUGGAGCCUCGGUGAGGGGGUGCGGGGGGCAAUGGCACUGCAGCUCUGGGCCCUGACCCUGCUGGGCCUGCUGGGCGCAGGUGCCAGCCUGAGGCCCCGCAAGCUGGACUUCUUCCGCAGCGAGAAAGAGCUGAACCACCUGGCUGUGGAUGAGGCCUCAGGCGUGGUGUACCUGGGGGCGGUGAAUGCCCUCUACCAGCUGGAUGCGAAGCUGCAGCUGGAGCAGCAGGUGGCCACGGGCCCGGCCCUGGACAACAAGAAGUGCACGCCGCCCAUCGAGGCCAGCCAGUGCCAUGAGGCUGAGAUGACUGACAAUGUCAACCAGCUGCUGCUGCUCGACCCUCCCAGGAAGCGCCUGGUGGAGUGCGGCAGCCUCUUCAAGGGCAUCUGCGCUCUGCGCGCCCUGAGCAACAUCUCCCUCCGCCUGUUCUACGAGGACGGCAGCGGGGAGAAGUCUUUCGUGGCCAGCAAUGAUGAGGGCGUGGCCACAGUGGGGCUGGUGAGCUCCACGGGUCCUGGUGGUGACCGCGUGCUGUUUGUGGGCAAAGGCAAUGGGCCACACGACAACGGCAUCAUCGUGAGCACUCGGCUGUUGGACCGGACUGACAGCAGGGAGGCCUUUGAAGCCUACACGGACCACGCCACCUACAAGGCCGGCUACCUGUCCACCAACACACAGCAGUUCGUGGCGGCCUUCGAGGACGGCCCCUACGUCUUCUUUGUCUUCAACCAGCAGGACAAGCACCCGGCCCGGAACCGCACGCUGCUGGCACGCAUGUGCAGAGAAGACCCCAACUACUACUCCUACCUGGAGAUGGACCUGCAGUGCCGGGACCCCGACAUCCACGCCGCUGCCUUUGGCACCUGCCUGGCCGCCUCCGUGGCUGCGCCUGGCUCUGGCAGGGUGCUAUAUGCUGUCUUCAGCAGAGACAGCCGGAGCAGUGGGGGGCCCGGUGCGGGCCUCUGCCUGUUCCCGCUGGACAAGGUGCACGCCAAGAUGGAGGCCAACCGCAACGCCUGUUACACAGGCACCCGGGAGGCCCGUGACAUCUUCUACAAGCCCUUCCACGGCGAUAUCCAGUGCGGCGGCCACGCGCCGGGCUCCAGCAAGAGCUUCCCAUGUGGCUCGGAGCACCUGCCCUACCCGCUGGGCAGCCGCGACGGGCUCAGAGGCACAGCCGUGCUGCAGCGUGGAGGCCUGAACCUCACGGCCGUGACGGUCGCCGCCGAGAACAACCACACUGUUGCUUUUCUGGGCACCUCUGAUGGCCGGAUCCUCAAGGUGUACCUCACCCCAGAUGGCACCUCCUCAGAGUACGACUCUAUCCUUGUGGAGAUAAACAAGAGAGUCAAGCGCGACCUGGUACUGUCUGGAGACCUGGGCAGCCUGUACGCCAUGACCCAGGACAAGGUGUUCCGGCUGCCGGUGCAGGAGUGCCUGAGCUACCCGACCUGCACCCAGUGCCGCGACUCCCAGGACCCCUACUGCGGCUGGUGCGUCGUCGAGGGACGAUGCACCCGGAAGGCCGAGUGUCCGCGGGCCGAGGAGGCCAGCCACUGGCUGUGGAGCCGAAGCAAGUCCUGCGUGGCCGUCACCAGCGCCCAGCCACAGAACAUGAGCCGGCGGGCCCAGGGGGAGGUGCAGCUGACCGUCAGCCCCCUCCCUGCCCUGAGCGAGGAGGACGAGUUGCUGUGCCUUUUUGGGGAGUCGCCGCCACACCCCGCCCGCGUGGAGGGCGAGGCCGUCAUCUGCAACUCCCCAAGCAGCAUCCCCGUCACACCGCCAGGCCAGGACCACGUGGCCGUGACCAUCCAGCUCCUCCUUAGACGAGGCAACAUCUUCCUCACGUCCUACCAGUACCCCUUCUACGACUGCCGCCAGGCCAUGAGCCUGGAGGAGAACCUGCCGUGCAUCUCCUGCGUGAGCAACCGCUGGACCUGCCAGUGGGACCUGCGCUACCACGAGUGCCGGGAGGCUUCGCCCAACCCUGAGGACGGCAUCGUCCGUGCCCACAUGGAGGACAGCUGUCCCCAGUUCCUGGGACCCAGCCCCCUGGUGAUCCCCAUGAACCACGAGACAGAUGUGAACUUCCAGGGCAAGAACCUGGACACCGUGAAGGGUUCCUCCCUGCACGUGGGCAGUGACUUGCUCAAGUUCAUGGAGCCGGUGACCAUGCAGGAAUCUGGGACCUUCGCCUUUCGGACCCCAAAGCUGUCCCACGAUGCCAACGAGACGCUGCCCCUGCACCUCUACGUCAAGUCUUACGGCAAGAAUAUCGACAGCAAGCUCCAUGUGACCCUCUACAACUGCUCCUUUGGCCGCAGCGACUGCAGCCUGUGCCGGGCCGCUAACCCCGACUACAGGUGUGCGUGGUGCGGGGGCCAGAGCAGGUGCGUGUAUGAGGCCCUGUGCAACACCACCUCCGAGUGCCCGCCGCCCGUCAUCACCAGGAUCCAGCCUGAGACGGGCCCCCUGGGUGGGGGCAUCCGCAUCACCAUCCUGGGGUCCAAUUUGGGCGUCCAAGCAGGGGACAUCCAGAGGAUCUCUGUGGCCGGCCGGAACUGCUCCUUUCAGCCGGAACGUUACUCCGUGUCCACCCGGAUCGUGUGUGUGAUCGAGGCUGCGGAGACGCCUUUCACGGGGGGUGUCGAGGUGGACGUCUUCGGGAAACUGGGCCGUUCGCCUCCCAAUGUCCAGUUCACCUUCCAACAGCCCAAGCCUCUCAGUGUGGAGCCGCAGCAGGGACCGCAGGCGGGCGGCACCACACUGACCAUCCACGGCACCCACCUGGACACGGGCUCCCAGGAGGACGUGCGGGUGACCCUCAACGGCGUCCCGUGUAAAGUGACGAAGUUUGGGGCGCAGCUCCAGUGUGUCACUGGCCCCCAGGCGACACGGGGCCAGAUGCUUCUGGAGGUCUCCUACGGGGGGUCCCCCGUGCCCAACCCCGGCAUCUUCUUCACCUACCGCGAAAACCCCGUACUGCGAGCCUUCGAGCCGCUACGAAGCUUUGCCAGUGGUGGCCGCAGCAUCAACGUCACGGGUCAGGGCUUCAGCCUGAUCCAGAGGUUUGCCAUGGUGGUCAUCGCGGAGCCCCUGCAGUCCUGGCAGCCGCCGCGGGAGGCUGAAUCCCUGCAGCCCAUGACGGUGGUGGGUACAGACUACGUGUUCCACAAUGACACCAAGGUCGUCUUCCUGUCCCCGGCUGUGCCUGAGGAGCCAGAGGCCUACAACCUCACGGUGCUGAUCGAGAUGGACGGGCACCGUGCCCUGCUCAGAACAGAGGCCGGGGCCUUCGAGUACGUGCCUGACCCCACCUUUGAGAACUUCACAGGUGGCGUCAAGAAGCAGGUCAACAAGCUCAUCCACGCCCGGGGCACCAAUCUGAACAAGGCGAUGACGCUGCAGGAGGCCGAGGCCUUCGUGGGUGCCGAGCGCUGCACCAUGAAGACGCUGACGGAGACCGACCUGUACUGUGAGCCCCCGGAGGUGCAGCCCCCGCCCAAGCGGCGGCAGAAACGAGACACCACACACAACCUGCCCGAGUUCAUUGUGAAGUUCGGCUCUCGCGAGUGGGUGCUGGGCCGCGUGGAGUACGACACACGGGUGAGCGACGUGCCGCUCAGCCUCAUCUUGCCGCUGGUCAUCGUGCCCAUGGUGGUCGUCAUCGCGGUGUCUGUCUACUGCUACUGGAGGAAGAGCCAGCAGGCCGAACGAGAGUAUGAGAAGAUCAAGUCCCAGCUGGAGGGCCUGGAGGAGAGCGUGCGGGACCGCUGCAAGAAGGAAUUCACAGACCUGAUGAUCGAGAUGGAGGACCAGACCAACGACGUGCACGAGGCCGGCAUCCCCGUGCUGGACUACAAGACCUACACCGACCGCGUCUUCUUCCUGCCCUCCAAGGACGGCGACAAGGACGUGAUGAUCACCGGCAAGCUGGACAUCCCUGAGCCGCGGCGGCCGGUGGUGGAGCAGGCCCUCUACCAGUUCUCCAACCUGCUGAACAGCAAGUCUUUCCUCAUCAAUUUCAUCCACACCCUGGAGAACCAGCGGGAGUUCUCGGCCCGCGCCAAGGUCUACUUCGCGUCCCUGCUGACGGUGGCGCUGCACGGGAAACUGGAGUACUACACGGACAUCAUGCACACGCUCUUCCUGGAGCUCCUGGAGCAGUACGUGGUGGCCAAGAACCCCAAGCUGAUGCUGCGCAGGUCUGAGACUGUGGUGGAGAGGAUGCUGUCCAACUGGAUGUCCAUCUGCCUGUACCAGUACCUCAAGGACAGUGCCGGGGAGCCCCUGUACAAGCUCUUCAAGGCCAUCAAACAUCAGGUGGAAAAGGGCCCGGUGGAUGCGGUACAGAAGAAGGCCAAGUACACUCUCAACGACACGGGGCUGCUGGGGGAUGAUGUGGAGUACGCACCCCUGACGGUGAGCGUGAUCGUGCAGGACGAGGGAGUGGACGCCAUCCCGGUGAAGGUCCUCAACUGUGACACCAUCUCCCAGGUCAAGGAGAAGAUCAUUGACCAGGUGUACCGUGGGCAGCCCUGCUCCUGCUGGCCCAGGCCAGACAGCGUGGUCCUGGAGUGGCGUCCGGGCUCCACAGCGCAGAUCCUGUCGGACCUGGACCUGACGUCACAGCGGGAGGGCCGGUGGAAGCGCGUCAACACCCUUAUGCACUACAAUGUCCGGGAUGGAGCCACCCUCAUCCUGUCCAAGGUGGGGGUCUCCCAGCAGCCGGAGGACAGCCAGCAGGACCUGCCUGGGGAGCGCCAUGCCCUCCUGGAGGAGGAGAACCGGGUGUGGCACCUGGUGCGGCCGACCGACGAGGUGGACGAGGGCAAGUCCAAGAGAGGCAGCGUGAAAGAGAAGGAGCGGACGAAGGCCAUCACCGAGAUCUACCUGACGCGGCUGCUCUCAGUCAAGGGCACACUGCAGCAGUUUGUGGACAACUUCUUCCAGAGCGUGCUGGCGCCUGGGCACGCGGUGCCACCUGCAGUCAAGUACUUCUUCGACUUCCUGGACGAGCAGGCAGAGAAGCACAACAUCCAGGAUGAAGACACCAUCCACAUCUGGAAGACGAACAGCUUACCGCUCCGGUUCUGGGUGAACAUCCUCAAGAACCCCCACUUCAUCUUUGACGUGCAUGUCCACGAGGUGGUGGACGCCUCGCUGUCAGUCAUCGCGCAGACCUUCAUGGAUGCCUGCACGCGCACGGAGCAUAAGCUGAGCCGCGAUUCUCCCAGCAACAAGCUGCUGUACGCCAAGGAGAUCUCCACCUACAAGAAGAUGGUGGAGGAUUACUACAAGGGGAUCCGGCAGAUGGUGCAGGUCAGCGACCAGGACAUGAACACACACCUGGCAGAGAUUUCCCGGGCGCACACGGACUCCUUGAACACCCUCGUGGCACUCCACCAGCUCUACCAAUACACGCAGAAGUACUAUGACGAGAUCAUCAAUGCCUUGGAGGAGGAUCCUGCCGCCCAGAAGAUGCAGCUGGCCUUCCGCCUGCAGCAGAUUGCCGCUGCACUGGAGAACAAGGUCACUGACCUCUGACCUACAAUCUCCAGUGCUGCCUUGGGACAUAGGUACCUGAGGUACCUGAGAGCCCCUCAGGGGAGGAGGCCGAGUGGCUGUGGCUGAGGCCCCCACCCUCCCCUGGAACGCGCCCCAAGCCGGAGUGGGUGCAGCCGGAACCCGCCCAGCGUCUAGACUGUAGCAUCUUCCUCUGAGCAAUACCGCCGGGCACCGCACCAGCACCAGCCCCAGCCCCAGCUCCCUCCGGCCGCAGAACCAGCAUCGGGUGUUCACUGUCGAGUCUCCAGUGAUUUGAAAAUGUGCCUUACGCUGCCACGCUGGGGGCAGCUGGCCUCCGCCUCCGCCCACGCACCAGCAGCCGCCUCCAUGCCCUAGGUUGGGCCCCUGGGGGAUCUGAGGGCCUGUGGCCCCCAGGGCAAGUUCCCAGAUCCUAUGUCUGUCUGUCCACCACGAGAUGGGAGGAGGAGAAAAAGCGGUACGAUGCCUUCCUGACCUCACCGGCCUCCCCAAGGGUGCCGGCACUCUGGGUGGACUCACGGCUGCUGGGCCCCACGUCAAAGGUCAAGUGAGACGUAGGUCAAGUCCUACGUCGGGGCCCAGACAUCCUGGGGUCCUGGUCUGUCAGACAGGCUGCCCUAGAGCCCCACCCAGUCCGGGGGGACUGGGAGCAGUUCCAAGACCACCCCACCCCUUUUUGUAAAUCUUGUUCAUUGUAAAUCAAAUACAGCGUCUUUUUCACUCUG